CAAAGGGAAGCGAAGCCGGAGCUGCGGGCGCUUUUUCUGCCCGCGGUGUCUCAGAUUCAUUCUUAAGGAACUGAGAACUUAAUCUUCCAAAAUGUCAAAAAGACCAUCUUAUGCCCCACCUCCCACCCCAGCUCCUGCAACACAAAUGCCCAGCACACCAGGGUUUGUGGGAUACAAUCCAUACAGUCAUCUCGCCUACAACAACUACAGGCUGGGAGGGAACCCGGGCACCAACAGCCGGGUCACGGCAUCCUCUGGUAUCACGAUUCCAAAACCCCCAAAGCCACCAGAUAAGCCGCUGAUGCCCUACAUGAGGUACAGCAGAAAGGUCUGGGACCAAGUAAAGGCUUCCAACCCUGACCUAAAGUUGUGGGAGAUUGGCAAGAUUAUUGGUGGCAUGUGGCGAGAUCUCACUGAUGAAGAAAAACAAGAAUAUUUAAACGAAUACGAAGCAGAAAAGAUAGAGUACAAUGAAUCUAUGAAGGCCUAUCAUAAUUCCCCCGCGUACCUUGCUUACAUAAAUGCAAAAAGUCGUGCAGAAGCUGCUUUAGAGGAAGAAAGUCGACAGAGACAAUCUCGCAUGGAGAAAGGAGAACCGUACAUGAGCAUUCAGCCUGCUGAAGAUCCAGAUGAUUAUGAUGAUGGCUUUUCAAUGAAGCAUACAGCCACCGCCCGUUUCCAGAGAAACCACCGCCUCAUCAGUGAAAUUCUUAGUGAGAGUGUGGUGCCAGACGUUCGGUCAGUUGUCACAACAGCUAGAAUGCAGGUCCUCAAACGGCAGGUCCAGUCCUUAAUGGUUCAUCAGCGAAAACUAGAAGCUGAACUUCUUCAAAUAGAGGAACGACACCAGGAGAAGAAGAGGAAAUUCCUGGAAAGCACAGAUUCAUUUAACAAUGAACUUAAAAGGUUGUGCGGUCUGAAAGUAGAAGUGGAUAUGGAGAAAAUUGCAGCUGAGAUUGCACAGGCAGAGGAACAGGCCCGCAAAAGGCAGGAGGAAAGGGAGAAGGAGGCCGCAGAGCAAGCUGAGCGCAGUCAGAGCAGCAUCGUUCCUGAGGAAGAACAAGCAGCUAACAAAGGCGAGGAGAAGAAAGACGACGAGAACAUUCCGAUGGAGACAGAGGAGACACACCUUGAAGAAACAACAGAGAGCCAACAGAAUGGUGAAGAAGGCACGUCUACUCCUGAGGACAAGGAGAGUGGGCAGGAGGGGGUCGACAGUAUGGCAGAGGAAGGAACCAGUGAUAGUAACACUGGCUCGGAGAGCAACAGUGCAACAGUGGAGGAGCCACCAACAGAUCCCAUACCAGAAGAUGAGAAAAAAGAAUAAGUGUUGCCUUGUUUUGUGUGUUCUAAAUACUUUUUUUAAUGAAAAAAUGUUUUUUGGUUUUAAUGGUGUUACGUGGUUUGUGUAUUAAUUUUUUUUCUUGUCCAUAUCACACCACCAAAGGCUUUUGGACCAUUUAGCAUCAUGAGCCUAAUGGCUCAGUCAGUCACCUUUCUUAAGUGUUGUGAAGAUGGCUCUUUUCUUUGGAUCUUGUUUCUAGCCCUCAACUGCUGAAAGCCUCAGAAUUUAGAUUAAUUGAGAAAACACCCACCUCUUUUAGAGAAUUAUCCUUUGAUGCUGCAGAAUCUACUCUUACAAUGCCUUCCUACAGCUCACUGGGGUGCUUACCAAAGCCAUAGCUUUAAACCUUCCCAGUCCCCAUCAGUAGCUUCCUGAAAGUCUCCUCUCUUGUUUACUUCUGCAAAGGGUAGCUUCUUAAAAACGUGAUCAUGUAUGAGUAUGUAUUUGUUCACUUACCCUUUUUUACUUUUAAUCAAUGUCAGAUACCAAGAGUUGUGUUAAGCUGAGUGUAGUGUGUAACUAACUACACUUGGAUCUUACUGAUCCAGAAAUAGUCCCCAUAGUUAGAGUAGUUACUUAUGAAGUGGUUAUUAAAGUGAACACAGCACAUAUACAUUAUCUAUACUGCUUUUUGUUAUGAUUAAUACUGGGUAUGUUCUGGUAAAUCCAUCCUUAUUGUAUAGAAAAAAAAUUACUUUUUUACCAGGUUUUCCAAAGACAGAAUAGAUCACAAAGCUCAAGGAAUUUAAUAUUCUUGUAAUGGACUAGAUAAUUCAAACUGAUUAGCCCAUUCCAGAAGAAAAACAGCUGGGAAUUAAGUUAAUCCACUUGAAAUUGUUUUACAAUAAUCAGAACAUCCAAACCUCAAGGCUCAGGAUCCCAUAGACCAGAGCCCACCUUUUUGAUAAACUUAGUAAAGUCUUGGAGACUAGAAGCAAGAUAGUUUGUGACACAUAAGCUUCCCAAAAACUAGAAUAGAUUUUUACUGAAUAGUGGUAUAUCUGAUGGUAUAUGUUUCUUAAAGGUCCAAAUGUAAUAAAAAAAAAAAUGAAAAAAAGGUCUCAGUGUUUUUAAUGCACUACAUAUUUGUAUGCAAGACAAGCAUCCAGUUUUUUUCUGUAAUGCAGUGACAGUGUGGAAUGACCACUCAGCCAUUAUAAAUUUGUGUACUCAGGGCCCUUGUCUCACCCAACUAUCUCUAUAAACUGCUGCAGUAGCUUAUUUGUACAAGACACUUGUGAAAAUCAGUUUUCUUACAUUAUAGUCAUUGUCACAUAUGGAAGUUGGUCUUUGAUUCCAAAAGUAAAGGGAAUAUGUUUCUACAUUAACAGGAAUAUGGAGAAAUCUGUAACGUUUGAAUUAUCUUUGAAAGAAUGGCUAAAUGAUAAAUGUUAAGUCCUGUGCCUAUAUGGAGAGGACUCUGUACCAGCAUGAGUUAAUUUAAGUGGAUUCACUGCUAUUCAGUUCAUAGCACAUUAGUGACUAGGAAUGUGUGUUCAGCCUCCUGAGAGAGGAGGGGAGGAAGCUUGAUACUGGGUGGAAACAACUCUUGACAUCUGUUUCCUUGUGUGUCAAAGAACGAAUUUGUAUCAAAUAGAUCUGUUUUGAGCUUUGGCCAUUAUUUGGCUAAGAACUUCAGCCAUCUCAUCUCAGACAAAUUGGACAGCCUCUUUGAUACAUUUUCUAGUAGUCAAAAUGGGGCAGAUGUAGUUUAAUAUGGGUGGAAAACUGCCCCAGCAAGAUACCAGGUUAUUUACUGUGGUAUCGAAAGCUCUAAGAGAAUGGAAGUGGUUCUUUUGCCCGGCUGGAAAUAGCAGUGGGAAGACAAGUCUAUCCAGACCAAGCCUGUCCAUACAACACUGGCAAUCAGUUGAUGAGGGAAUUAAGUCAGAUGGGAGACGUCUCAAUCUGUCGCCCAGGUUGGAGUGCAGUGGUGGCGAUCUCAGCUCACUGCAACCUCCACCUCCCAGGUUCAAGCAAUUCUCUCUGCCUCAGCCUCUAGAGCAGCUGGGAUUACAGGCUCUCGCCACCAUGCCCGGUUAAUUUUUGUAUUUUUUAGUAGAGAUGGGGUUUCACCAUGUUAGCCAGGCUGAUCUUGAACUCGUGACCUCAGGUGAUCCGCCUGCCUCAGUCUCCCAAAGUGCUGGGAUUACAGGCGUGAGCCACUGUGCCCGGCCUCAGUUGGGAUUUGACAGCUCUGAACCUCAGCAGGGGAAGAUUGAUGUAAAAAUCCACUUGGUCAGAGUGAUAUAUGUAGACUUGAUGUUUGAGAUGGUUCUCAGUUUAGAGAAUGUGGGAUAUGGUAGAGGUCUUUGUUUUUUUCCCAUGUCCCAAAAGGUGCUGGGCAAGUAGCUUGAACUCGAGCCUGUUUUAAUUAUAAAAUAGAUCAAACUGCUCUUUCUUGGUGCCCUUACUGCUCCUUGAUUUUUAGUGCAUUUAUUUUGAGUAUGAAUGCAUAAAGUCUGAGGGCCUAAAUUUUGUUAAUUUUUUUUAACAAAUGGGAGAGGGGAAUCCUCGAUAGUCACCCAAUUUUCCUUUUUUUUUGAGACAGUCUGACUGUUGCCCAGGCUGGAGUGUAAUGGCGCCAUCUCGGCUCACUGCAACAUCCAGCUCCUGGGUUUCAGCAAUUCUCCUGCCUCAGCCUCCUGAGUAGCUGGGAUUACAGGCGCCCGCCACCACGCCCGGCUAAUUUUUGUAUUUUUAGUAGAGACAGGAUUUUGCCAUGUUUGCCAGCCUGGUCUCGAACUCUUGACCUCCUGAUCCACCCUCCUCUGCCUCCCAAAGUGCUGGGAUUACAGGCGUGAGCCACCGCGCCCAGCCCCAUAGUCCCCCAAUUUUCUAACAGUUUUAAAUUCUGUAACUUCUCCUGUCUGUAAACAAGGCUGUCUUUUCAAAUGGCUCUCCUACAGGAUGUGAUAAUUAUCUAUUCUAUAAAGCCGAGGUUUGGAGAGGUAAAUAGCUAUUUCACAUUAACACAAUAAUGUCAAUGCCCUAUGGAAAAGAUAAAAUACUUGGACUAUAUUUUAAAGGGGAAUCUGGGGUCAUGCAUAUUGAAGUUUAACUAGAUCCCUCCAGAUUUUUGGUUUUGAUCCUACACAUUUAGAUACUAGUUUUGGAUUUUAGACAGUUGGUGCUGACAGUGUGAAACUCCUAUUGCCUGCAGUUAAAUUGAAGCUUUGGUUUCUCGUGAACAGGCAGUGAAGCUGGUAUUAUACUUUAAGUCCUCAUUUCAGAAAUAGUUUCCCUCCACCCCCAAGCACUACCACACAUGGUCUCCCCACCUGGUUUCAGCUAGUGCAUUAGUUUUAUCUUGUUUUUUACCGCUGGGCAAACCUUGCUGGAACAACAACUGACUUCAUGAUUUGCACAUUUGGAGGGCUUAACGUCUUUGCAAAUGAAAAAUCCACUGUACAAUAACAAGCUCAAAGGAACUCGGAGCCUUUUUAGAAGAAAUCGUGCUGAAUUAUAAUGUGGCUUACUGCAAUAAUGUUUCUUUGAUCAGGAUGGAAAGGAAAAUACUGAGUUUAGCAGAAAACGAUGUCUAAAUGUAUUUGUAAUGAUACAAUUGUUUAUAAAUGUUUUACUAUUAGGUUGAACCAUAAGAAAUUGCCAGUGUACAAUUUCAUCUACAAAAUGACUGGCUUAACCUAAAUUCUGCAUUUUAUACUCCAAGAAUAAGCUCUUCGUGGCAGCUUUCUAAGUGUGAAAUGAUGGAACUUUCUAUUUGCCAGAAUGACCUACACUUCUCUAAUAGUUUAUCUCAUAUUGUUAGCCAAACGCUGAUUAAAAUGCAAAUUUCAAACUA